CCCGGCGCUCCUCAAGAUGGCUGCCGACAGUGAGCCCGAAUCCGAGGUAUUUGAGAUCACGGACUUCACCACUGCCUCGGAAUGGGAAAGGUUUAUUUCCAAAGUUGAAGAAGUCUUGAAUGACUGGAAACUGAUUGGAAACUCUUUGGGAAAGCCACUCGAAAAGGGUAUAUUUACUUCUGGCACAUGGGAAGAGAAAUCAGAUGAAAUUUCCUUUGCUGACUUCAAGUUCUCAGUCACUCAUCAUUAUCUUGUACAAGAGUCCACUGAUAAAGAAGGAAAGGAUGAGUUAUUAGAGGAUGUUGUUCCACAAUCUAUGCAAGAUUUGCUGGGUAUGAAUAAUGACUUUCCUCCAAGAGCACAUUGCCUGGUAAGAUGGUAUGGGCUACGUGAGUUCGUGGUGAUUGCCCCUGCUGCACACAGUGACGCUGUUCUCAGCGAAUCUAAGUGCAACCUUCUUCUGAGUUCUGUUUCUAUUGCCUUGGGAAACACUGGCUGUCAGGUGCCACUCUUUGUGCAAAUUCACCACAAAUGGCGAAGAAUGUAUGUAGGAGAAUGUCAAGGUCCUGGUGUACGAACUGAUUUCGAAAUGGUUCAUCUUAGAAAAGUGCCAAAUCAGUACACUCACUUAUCAGGUCUGCUGGAUAUCUUCAAAUCAAAGAUUGGAUGUCCUUUAACUCCAUUGCCUCCAGUUAGUAUUGCUAUUCGAUUUACCUAUGUACUUCAAGAUUGGCAGCAGUAUUUUUGGCCUCAGCAACCUCCAGACAUAGAUGCCCUUGUAGGAGGAGAAGUUGGAGGCUUGGAGUUUGGCAAGUUACCAUUUGGUGCCUGCGAAGAUCCUAUUAGUGAACUCCAUUUAGCUACUACAUGGCCUCAUCUGACCGAAGGGAUCAUUGUGGAUAAUGAUGUUUAUUCUGAUUUGGAUCCUAUUCAAGCUCCACAUUGGUCUGUUAGAGUUCGAAAAGCUGAGAAUCCUCAGUGUUUGCUAGGUGAUUUUGUCACUGAAUUUUUUAAAAUUUGCCGUCGAAAGGAGUCAACUGAUGAGAUUCUUGGACGAUCUGCAUUUGAGGAAGAAGGCAAAGAAACUGCUGAUAUAACUCAUGCUUUGUCAAAAUUGACAGAGCCGGCAUCAGUUCCAAUUCAUAAAUUAUCAGUUUCAAAUAUGGUACACACUGCAAAGAAGAAAAUCCGAAAACACAGAGGUGUAGAGGAGUCACCGCUAAAUAAUGAUGUUCUUAAUACUAUUCUCCUGUUCUUAUUCCCUGAUGCUGUUUCUGAGAAACCAUUAGAUGGAACUACUUCAACAGAUAAUAAUAAUCCUCCAUCAGAGAGUGAAGACUAUAAUCUCUACAAUCAGUUCAAGUCUGCACCAUCUGACAGUUUAACAUACAAACUGGCUUUGUGUCUCUGUAUGAUCAAUUUUUACCAUGGAGGGUUGAAAGGAGUGGCACACCUCUGGCAGGAAUUUGUUCUUGAAAUGCGUUUCCGAUGGGAAAACAACUUUCUGAUUCCAGGAUUAGCAAGUGGACCCCCAGAUCUGAGGUGUUGUUUACUGCAUCAGAAACUACAGAUGUUAAAUUGUUGUAUUGAAAGAAAGAAGGCACGUGAUGAGGGGAAAAAGACAAGUGCUUCAGAUGUCACUAAUAUAUAUCCAGGGGAUGCUGGAAAAGCAGGAGACCAGUUGGUGCCAGAUAAUCUAAAAGAAACAGAUAAGGAAAAGGGAGAGGUAGGAAAAUCUUGGGAUUCCUGGAGUGACAGCGAAGAAGAAUUUUUUGAAUGCCUAAGUGAUACUGAAGAACUUAAAGGAAAUGGACAAGAGAGUGGCAAGAAAGGAGGACCUAAGGAGAUGGCAAAUUUAAGGCCGGAAGGACGGCUCUAUCAGCAUGGGAAACUUACACUGCUGCAUAAUGGAGAACCUCUCUACAUUCCAGUAACCCAGGAACCAGCACCUAUGACAGAAGAUCUGCUAGAAGAGCAGUCUGAAGUUUUAGCUAAAUUAGGUACAUCGGCAGAGGGGGCUCACCUUCGAGCACGCAUGCAGAGUGCCUGUCUGCUCUCAGAUAUGGAGUCUUUUAAGGCAGCUAAUCCAGGUUGCUCCCUGGAAGAUUUUGUGAGGUGGUAUUCACCCCGGGAUUAUAUUGAAGAGGAGGUGAUUGAUGAAAAGGGCAAUGUGGUGCUGAAAGGAGAACUGAGUGCCCGGAUGAAGAUUCCAAGCAAUAUGUGGGUAGAAGCCUGGGAAACAGCUAAGCCAAUUCCUGCUAGAAGGCAAAGGAGACUCUUUGAUGAUACACGGGAAGCAGAAAAGGUGCUGCACUAUCUGGCAAUCCAGAAACCUGCAGACCUUGCUCGGCACCUGUUACCUUGUGUGAUUCAUGCAGCUGUACUCAAGGUAAAGGAAGAAGAAAGUCUCGAAAACAUUUCUUCAGUUAAGAAGAUCAUAAAGCAGAUAAUAUCCCAUUCCAGUAAAGUUUUGCACUUCCCCAAUCCAGAAGACAAGAAAUUGGAAGAAAUCAUUCACCAGAUUACUAAUGUGGAAGCUCUCAUUGCCAGAGCUCGGUCACUAAAAGCCAAGUUUGGAACUGAGAAAUGUGAACAGGAGGAGGAAAAGGAAGAUCUUGAAAGGUUUGUGAGUUGCCUGCUGGAGCAGCCUGAAGUGUUAGUCACCGGUGCAGGAAGAGGACAUGCUGGCAGGAUCAUUCACAAGCUGUUUGUGAAUGCCCAGAGGCUGACUGAAUCUUCUGAUGAGGCUGCAGCUAUGACUCCACCAGAGGAGGAAUUGAAGAGAAUGGGCUCCCCAGAGGAAAGAAGGCAGAACUCCGUGUCAGACUUCCCACCCCCUGCUGGCCGGGAAUUCAUUUUGCGCACCACUGUGCCGCGCCCUGCUCCCUACUCCAAAGCUCUGCCUCAGCGGAUGUACAGUGUUCUCACCAAAGAGGACUUUAGACUUGCAGGUGCCUUUUCAUCAGAUACUUCCUUCUUCUGAUUCUUCUAGCAUUACUCGUUGGUGGCUUCAGAGACAGUGCUGCCUCCUCCUGAGGGAGGGAAGGUACCAGGGAGAACCUGGGAGGUCCUGGAGAGGGCCCUGUCCAGUUGGGUGAUCAGGAAUCAAACCAGCAUCGGAAAGACUUCCCAGCACCAAGCUUGAGCUGUGUCGUUUCGUGGAGGGGGCAGCGAGGAUGGGCUUGAGCUGUUGAGAGAUUUCUGCCCUAGAGAUGGCCUUUGUAUAUGGGGGGGUGGUGGGGGGACACAAACACAUCAGACACUCCGUCCUCACACUGGCAGGACGGUGUUCAUCGCAUUCUCUUCUGUGACCAGCCUCUAGGCUAGCGGCUGCAUUCGUGGUCUGUGCAAACACUUCGUGGUUCUAUAUAUCAGCAGCAAGUGUGCAAAAUAAAGGACCUGUUAACUCAGAUUUCUGGAUAUUUUGGUGGUAGCUUCUAGUCCCAGAAUCUGUGUUUUUAAAAUACUACAUGACAUUCUGUCUAUUCAAUCACCUGGUGGUCAUCUUUCUUGUACUAAUUAACUGUUGAUGAGCAUUUUGGAUAUUCUAGGAGAAAGCCUAUAAUUUCACAUAGUUUCUCUUUUUCAUGUAACUGUAACCUAAAUGUAUUACUUCUGAUAAAACUAUAUAUCAAAUGUCACUGCAAAUUAGUUUUAUAUCUGUCAUGUGAGAUUUGUCUUACUUAUUUUUCUUUUGGUUGCCAUGGAAGUUAUGGCCCUGAAAAUCGUCUCCCUCCCCUUCUCUUGCUGUACAGCAUGCGUUCUCUUUUUGUGGUUGCUGGCUGGGUACUGUAUUUAAUGAAGUAGAGAAUAGCACUUGCAAAAAUACAGUCUUGGUACCUAGAGACUGUCAUGCAGAUAGUAUAAUUUGGUAUAUGUGCUAAUGCAUUGAGUAGAGGAUUAUUUUAACACACUAUUUUGCUUUUGUAUUUUAGUUAAAAUAAUCGAUGGGGAUGUGUAGCCCCCCCGUGUGAGGAUGACAUCACCACAUUUCUAGUUUCAUGGAGCUCAAGAUGUCUUGUGUCUGUGUGGCUAGAUGGCCUCUGCUUGGUAAUCUUAUUUUUAGGCCUAAAAUUCCCACUUAAAUCCAAAGUAAAAAUGGUUAUACUGAAGCAUAAACCUUGCCUGUGUAAUUUUAAAAAAUUAAUAGAGCUGUGCAAACCCUGUUAUUUUUGUAAAAAAAAAAAAAAAUACAUAUCUAUAUAUAAUAUGUGUGUGUGUGUGACAUAUGCACACGUCUCUGUGUAUGUGAAGUAGGGGAGGCCCUGGGGGAUGACCUCCCAGCCUUUAUGAUGCUUUUCUCUAUGCUGCUGGACUUCAUUCUUACUGGUCCACGCAGAUGCAGGCGGCCUGAGGCCAGUGCUGUACCAAGUAGAAGACGGUUCCUAAGGACAGAGUUUGUCUGUUUUCUAACAAAGAAAAAUUCUACAAAGGAGAGGUUGGGCGUUACAAAGGCAUUGUGAAUCUAAUAAAAGGAAAGUGUCGCUUUCUGUGGCGUUUUCUUUCAUUUUCUCCCGCUGAGGCAUUUCAGUCUAAUUUCAUGUGGUUUUGUGCUGUCUCAGCUCUAAUGUUUGCAGCCUGCUGAGCCUAACAAGGCAGUGGUCUCAAGAACAUUCUUUGUGCCUUUUUAAAGUACUCCAUUUUAUUUUUAUGAUAGUUAUGUAUUUAUUUCACAGAUAUAUUUAAGUACCCACUUUGUGUCAGGUACAGUACAAGCAAUGAAGAUAAAACAGAAACCAAAACACACUCCCUUACAGGGAAAACUGACACCACGUUGCCACAAAAUGUUGAGUAUAGUCAACUCUGCUGUGUGGAUCGGAGGGCCUGCAUUUAUCCUACAAAUAAUUGAAUGUAAUCCUACAUUCAUGUAUUCAUUGGCAGUACGGAGUAAUAAAUGCAGCAAUGUCAUAAA